AUGUUAGAGAAGGGAGCCCUAGAUCUGGCCACCAGCGGCCUGUGCACACCUGGGGCUGAGGGCACACAGGGCUGCACAUACACACUCAAGGCCACUGUGAGAACAGGUGAGCAGGGCCAGAGGGCUAUGGAAAGCCCGGCUGAAGGCUGCACCUCCAGGCUGAAGAGAGCUUUACCGGCAUCCGCCAGGAAGCCUGGGCUCUGGGGCUGUGUCAUUGUAGAUGACCAUUUCCAGGUCGUGGCCACAGCCCCGGUUCUGGUCACAGCUGGGCCACCAAUCCUCCUGCGCCACCCACCACUUAGCCAUCGGGCCGUCUUCAGGGCAUCGGCCGGCCUCAGCUGCUGCAGCCAGACCCUGGCGUUGCGGAAGGCUGGCCAGUCCACAUCCUGCAGCCUACGAGGAGGUCAGGUCUUUGUCAGCAAAGGUGGGAAACCAGGGGAGCGGCGGCACCAGGCUCCAGAGACAUUUGAAAUGACUUCAGAAGACCCAGGGCCACUCAGGGUGACCACAUCGGACAGCUGCCUCCCACAGGCUGUGACGGAUGUUUAAGCAAGGGAUCGAUGGUCACCUGACUCUCAGGAGUGCAGGAGAGGCCACUGAGACCCAUUCAGAAGGGACUGGGUGUUGGUCCCUGUGGACUCGGCCUCUGGCUGGUGGUGAGGAGGAGGAUUUCUCACCACCCAUCCUCUGGCCCCUGCUGCCCAAGGGAGCAGACUCCUGUGAGCUGGGUUCCGGGAAGUCCGUCUCCAGCAGGAACUCCAGGCCAAGCGCGCAUCUCUGUGAUCGUGUGUCACCAUGGCGGUGCGUGCGUGAGUGCAUGCGUGUGCACUGGUCUGUGGCCUGUGGUGCGUGAGUUCCACUAGGACCCAUGUGAGGUGGAGGGUCUUCCACCUCCCCUCCCAUUCGGGCCCUCCCUGUGCCACACAGACACCCAUCUGUGCCUUCCCCUUCUGUGCCACCAAAAAUGGAAGAGAUAGACACUUAAAAGAAGCAACUCAAAUGGAAUGAAAUCGUUUCUGUUGGGGAAUGCUCAAGACGUUCAAUCAUCUUAGAAAAUCCCACCCCACCUCCCGCUGCAGAUUAAUUACUGUAAGUGCAACUCCAAUCGGGCUGGUGACCCCCCAGGAAACCUCUGAAGCUGUCCCAGGCUGUUCCCAACAUGGGACCUCCACUCUGGCACACCAGGACCCGAGGCCCCUGACAGGCUCCUCGUUCCUGCCUCGCUCAAGGCUCAGGUCCCCCACCUGAAAUACCCCCUCCCACCAGCAUCUCCUGCCUCGCUCCUGCUGCCAGGUCCCCAAAAGCUCUUGUUCAUGAGCUCGCCUGCCAUCCACAGCCCCCACCAGAACCCAAGUGGCUGUGGAAUUCGCUGCCCUGAUUCUCUGCCCAGAGCCUCGGUCCAGACUGUGUUCCCUGGCGAAUUAGUGUUCAGCAUUUUUGUUUAUUUGUUUGUUCUUUAACAAAAGUUGUUUUGGUUUGAGAUUCAGCAAAAAUACACACUGCAUUCAGCUUCCUCUCCAUUCAGGAUUCAGUAAAUUGGUUGUUUUCCUGUC